AGAGAACAGCCUGAGUGGCCGCAGUGUUGAGGCCCUAAGGACAAAGCUCCUUCACAGGGCAUUUGCAUUUACCGCAACCUGGAGGUCAGUGUUCUCUUCCGGACGUCUCCAUUCUGCCCGGGACCGGGUGCUCAGCCCCAACACAGUGGCAGUCCAAUGGGCUGAGGACAGAAGCAACUGCUGCUCUCAUCUGCCUUCCAUCUGGUGGACCUAAGCCUAAUCCCUGGGACAAGGAUGGUGGGUGCCAAGGCCGGCCCCAGCCCCGGCACCUCCCUGGGCCUGGCACAGCAGCACAGCGGAGGCAGCAGUGUCCUAGUGAAAAGUCCCUUCUGUCAGGUGUGCUGCUGUGGGCCUGCUCCUUGUGCCAGCUGCUGCCACUCUAGGUGGCCCUCUCUCACCGCAUCCACUUGCAGCCGCCUGUUCUACAUCCUCCUCCAUGUGGGGGCCUCAGCAAUCUGCUGCCUCCUGCUGUCAAGGACAGUAGUGGAAAGGGUGUGGGGCAAGACACACAGGAUCCAGAUGCCCUCGGGGUUGUGUGCCCACCUGUUUGGCCUCUCUGACUGUCCAGUGCUCAGUGGCUCUGGGGCUGUGUACCGAGUAUGUGCAGGAACCGCCACCUUCCACCUGCUGCAGGCUGUGUUGCUGGUCCACCUCCACUCCCCCACCAGCCCGCGGGCACAGCUGCAUAAUAGCUUCUGGCUCCUCAAGCUGCUGUUCCUGUUAGGUCUCUGUGCUAUUGCCUUCUGCAUUCCUGAUGAGCAUCUCUUCCCAGCAUGGCAUUACAUUGGCAUCUGUGGAGGCUUUGCAUUCAUCCUACUGCAGUUGGUGCUUAUUACAGCUUUUGCCCAUUCCUGGAACAAGAACUGGCAGACAGGUGCAGCUCAAGACUGUAGCUGGUUCCUGGCUGUCCUGCUGGCCACCCUAGGAUUCUACAGCAUGGCAGGUGUGGGAGCUGUGCUCCUAUUCCACUAUUAUACACACCCAGCUGGCUGCCUGCUUAACAAGAUGCUCCUCAGUCUGCACCUUUGCUUCUGUGGCCUCAUCUCCUUCCUCUCCAUCGCUCCUUGCAUCCGCCUCAAGCAACCCCGCUCUGGCCUCCUACAAGCUUCUGUCAUCAGCUGCUAUAUCAUGUAUCUGACUUUCUCUGCACUGUCCAGCCGUCCUCCAGAGAGAGUAAUCCUUCAAGGACAGAAUCACACCCUGUGCCUGCCUGGCCUGAGUAAAAUGGAACCCCAAACACCAGAUAUCUCUCUAGCAAUGCUGAGUGCUAGCAUCAUGUAUGCUUGUGUGCUUUUUGCUUGCAAUGAGGCCUCCUACCUGGCUGAGGUAUUUGGACCCCUGUGGAUUGUCAAGGUUUACAGCUAUGAGUUUCAGAAGCCCUCACUGUGUUUCUGCUGCCCUGAAACAGUGGAGGCAGACAAAGGGCAAAGGGGUGGGGCUGCGAGGCCAGCUGACCAAGAAACCCCUCCAGCUCCUCCAGUCCAAGUCCAGCAUCUUUCCUACAACUAUUCUGCCUUCCACUUCGUCUUCUUCCUUGCCUCACUCUAUGUCAUGGUUACCCUUACCAACUGGUUCAGCUAUGAGGGAGCAGAACUGGAAAAGACCUUCAUCAAGGGUAGCUGGGCCACCUUCUGGGUCAAGGUUGCCUCAUGCUGGGCCUGCGUACUCCUCUAUCUGGGGCUGUUACUGGCACCACUCUGUUGGCCCCCCACCCAGAAACCCCAGCCCCUUAUCUUGAGGCGCCGCCGCCACCGCAUCAUAUCCCCAGAUAACAAAUAUCCUCCAGUCUAAGUCCUUUUCACAAACUGGGGUUCCCCUGACAUUGUACUCCUAGAGUUGGCUCAAGGGGAGCUGUCCAGCCCAGCUCAAUACCUCAAGGACACACAGGGAGUUAUCUCCGUUUGGGCUGAAGUCAAUACUAUGAACUGGAAGAAGUGGUCAAACACAGUCUAAUGUGCUGGGCAGAGUGUCUGACUCACUGGAGCUACUGUUACAUCUGCAUCCCAGCUCAAGAGCCUAACACCCAAAUCAGCAGCUCAAAGAACCACCGCUGAUCCCAGCAGACAGUGUGGCACCAGCCCUUUCCUGGCUCUUGGGCUGGAAGUGGGGGUGGGGAAAGACCAACAGGGACUGAAGACUCGGCUCUGCCCUUGGAGAAAGGAAAAUAAGGAGUUCAGCCCUGGGCACACGGAUAUAAGAAGCCCAGAACCACAGAACAAACCAGGGCAUAGAAGAAAGGAGCACAGAGGCUACCCCAGGUUUUAAUCCUGAUUUUGAGGUCAAGGGAAGCGGGAAGACAAAACCACCCUCAUUCCAUGAGGAAUGACAGAAGAGAAAGUGAACGCUUGACAGCAGCUGACCACGGGAAGUCGGUGAGCAGCAGGAUUUUUUGGCCAACUUUCAAGCAGACGAACAAACUGAGGAAGAAUGAGGAAAAGAGGCAUAAACACAGAUCUUGCAGCAUUCACUCUUAGGCCAACUCCAUCCUAGAGAUGGUGUUCAAGGGUGGGGAACAAAAAUCACAGAAAAGAAGUCUCUAUGGUUCUUAGAGGAUUCCUCUACUGCAUAUCCGGAGUACUUGUUUGGUUGUCAUUGUAUAAUAAAGGCUUCUUCUGUGAUGUUUCACUUA